AUUCAAAUUGCGGCCUUCUGGGGAGCCGGCGCUGGAGGUGGUGAGUGGCGUGGGGACUGUGUCGAGGGGGUCCCCAAGGUGCCGGACCCUGCGGAGGGGCGAAGUUUCGGCACUGGGGAGGGCGUGCGGACGCUUUCCCUACAGGCGACCACUGCUCUGCGGGCGGGUGGUCUUAGCUCCAGUCCCCCAUUCAGUUCCUCAGCAUUCCAGGUCGGCGGCGAAGGGGUCCCCGAACGAAGGGCGCAAGGCAGCGUCUCUGCUGGGACCGGGAAGCCGGACUUCAGGGCCUCUCGGCCCGUGGGCUUCUCCCCGAGUCUCCCCGAGUCGGUUGGCAUUAAGAGGUAAUUCUUAGUCAUAGCCCCUGGUAAUGACUAGCAGAGAAAGAACAGAAUCACCGGAUGUUUUGGUUUGGAUUGUGCUUAUUUUCCUUGUAUUCCUUCCAGUCCUCUUUAAAAUCUGAUGGCGAAACUCCUCAAACAGAAACCGUAUUGAUUUGUGCAAAUCGCAAAUGGUUUUUAGUUGCAAGAGAAUUUCCAGAAUCUUCUUUUUGCCUUUAAAUUCAUUUCAUAACAGGAAAAUUCUGUAUUUUGAGUUGAAACGUUGAUGGGAGAUGCUUAUAAGCUGACGAAUUUUUUUUGUAAUGACUGUUAUUUAUGUAAAAAUUUAAAAGCCUCAUUUAAAAAUGAACUUCCAUUAAUUUGUUCCUCGCUAGCAAUAAUCUUUGCAAUAGUUUGAACCAGUGUCAUUUUACAGGUUAGAACCCGGCAUGCAAAUUUAAAGUCUUGUUUACAUCCUUGUAAGGAGUUGGAUACAAAGCUGACUAAAAGCCAGGUCUCUUAGCUGUCACUGCUGUUCCCUUUCUUUAAAACGUUAAUACCUGAUAGAUAUUGUUGCUGUAUAUUUACAUACACCUCUGUCUAAUUUGUUGUCUUACUGCUAAAGGGCAGGUUGUCUGUUUAUCUAAUCUUGCAUGGUUUUUCUCAACACAAUUAAUUUACAGUACUUAUCGUACUUACUGCCUGUGGUACUUGGGAAUAAUCUGCCUCGUGACACCAAUCAAUUCAAUCUUCUCUAUAGGCAUUCCUGUAUUCAACAUACAUGGGCCGGACGCGGUGGCUCACGCCUGUAAUCCCAGCACUUUGGGAGGCCGAGGCGGGCGGAUCACAAGGUCAAGAUAUCGAGACCAUCCUGGCCAACAUGGUGAAACCCCGUCUCUACUAAAAAUACAAAAAUUAGCUGGGCAUGGUGGUGGGCGCCUGUAGUCCCAGCUACUUGGGAGGCUAAGGCAGGAGAUUUGCUUGAAUACAGGAGGAGGAGGUUGCAGCAAGCCAAGGUCGUGCCACUGCACUCCAGCCUGGUGACAGAGCAAGACUCCAUCUCAAAAAAAAUAUUUUUAUAAAAAUAAAAUAAAAUAAACCUUCUUAUGGAACAUUGGCAAAAAAAAAAAAUACGUGUAGCAGGUAUUUAUAAAAAUACUUUGCUCCACACUCUGAUUUAGGUGCUAGGGUUUCCUUUAGUCCUUCCCAUUCCCCACACUGGAAGUACUUGAAAAUCUAUGUUGGCAUGCACUUUUUACAUCUUCUAAGUCACUUGACACAUUUGGCCUGAUAUAUGGCUUAUCAGUAUAUUUCUUCUAGACUAAAGAAAUGGGAAUUGUAUUCUUGUCUUUGAAGUCUACAGUAUCUAUCAGAGGGCCUGGCACUAAUGGAAACUUAGUCAAUAUUUGUUGAAUAAUGAUGGUAAGUUCUCUGAGAGACUUGCCUGAAGUUGCUUGGAAGCAGUAUCUGAGCUGCAGAUUGUGAUCUAUUGUAAUGUAUGCCUCUGGGAAUUUACUUACACAAUGGGAUGUUCUCUCUAUAUUUUUAAAGCUUGUUUGUAGUCUGUGUGAUCUAAAUCUUUUUUUUUUCUUUUAGUUUAGCAGAUACUUUCAGAAAUGGAUACAUAAGAAAUGGCUGGAAAUCAAAUGAAUGUCCAAAGAAGAGCUUAGGGUCUUAGUAACAUUCUUUUUUAAAAUAACUGUCUGCCAAAAUGUCAUUACACAGUACUCAUAAUAGAAAUAACAGCGGUGAUAUUCUUGAUAUUCCUUCUUCCCAAAAUAGUUCAUCACUGAAUGCCCUCACCCACAGUAGCCGACUUAAGCUGCAUUUGAAGUCGGAUAUGUCAGAAUGUGAAAAUGAUGAUCCAUUAUUGAGAUCUGCAGGUAGAUUGGCACUUCAGAGGAGAACUACAAGGAACAAAGAAUCAUCUUUGCUUGUUAGUGAGUUGGAAGACACAACUGAAAAAACAGCAGAAACACGUCUUACAUUACAACGUCGUGCUAAAACAGAUUCUGCAGAAAAGUGGAAAACAGCUGAAAUAGAUUCUGUCAAAAUGACACUGAAUGUGGGAGGUGAAACAGAAAAUAAUGGUGUUUCUAAGGAAAGUAGAACAAAUGUAAGGAUUGUAAAUAAUGCUAAAAACUCUUUUGUUGCCUCUUCUGUACCUUUAGAUGAAGAUCCACAGGUCAUUGAAAUGAUGGCUGAUAAGAAAUACAAAGAAACAUUUUCUGCCCCCAGUAGAGCAAAUGAAAAUGUUGCACUUAAGUACUCAAGUAAUAGACCACCCAUUGCUUCCCUGAGUCAGACUGAAGUUGUUAGAUCAGGACACUUGACAACGAAACCUACUCAGAGCAAGUUGGAUAUCAAAGUGUUGGGAACAGGAAACUUGUAUCAUAGAAGUAUUGGGAAGGAAAUUGCAAAAACUUCAAAUAAAUUUGGGAGCUUAGAAAAAAGAACACCUACAAAAUGUACAACAGAACACAAACUGACAACAAAGUGCAGCCUGCCUCAGCUUAAGAGCCCAGCUCCAUCAAUACUGAAGAAUAGAAUGUCUAACCUUCAAGUUAAACAAAGACCAAAAAGUUCCUUUCUUGCAAAUAAACAGGAAAGAUCCGCAGAAAAUACAAUUCUUCCCGAAGAAGAAACUGUAGUUCAGAACACCUCUGCAGGAAAAGACCCCUUAAAAGUAGAGAAUAGUCAAGUGACAGUGGCAGUACGCGUAAGACCUUUCACCAAGAGAGAGAAGAUUGAAAAAGCAUCCCAGGUAGUCUUCAUGAGUGGGAAAGAAAUAACUGUGGAACACCCUGACACGAAACAAGUUUAUAAUUUUAUUUAUGAUGUUUCAUUCUGGUCUUUUGAUGAAUGUCAUCCUCACUACGCUAGCCAGACAACUGUCUAUGAGAAGCUAGCAGCACCACUCCUAGAAAGAGCCUUCGAAGGCUUCAAUACCUGUCUUUUUGCUUAUGGUCAGACUGGCUCUGGAAAAUCAUAUACGAUGAUGGGAUUUAGUGAAGAACCAGGAAUAAUUCCAAGAUUUUGUGAAGAUCUUUUUUCUCAAGUAGCCAGAAAACAAACCCAAGAGGUCAGCUAUCACAUUGAAAUGAGCUUCUUUGAAGUAUAUAAUGAAAAAAUUCACGACCUUCUGGUUUGUAAAGAUGAAAAUGGGCAGAGAAAGCAACCACUGAGAGUGAGGGAACAUCCUGUUUAUGGACCAUAUGUUGAAGCACUGUCAAUGAACAUUGUCAGUUCUUACGCUGAUAUCCAGAGUUGGCUAGAAUUGGGAAAUAAACAAAGAGCUACUGCUGCUACUGGUAUGAAUGAUAAAAGUUCCCGAUCUCAUUCAGUUUUCACCCUGGUGAUGACCCAGACCAAGACAGAAUUUGUGGAAGGGGAAGAACACGAUCACAGAAUAACAAGUCGAAUUAACCUAAUAGAUCUGGCAGGCAGUGAGCGCUGCUCUACGGCUCACACUAAUGGAGAUCGACUAAAGGAAGGUGUGAGUAUUAAUAAGUCCUUGCUAACUUUGGGAAAAGUUAUAUCUGCACUUUCGGAACAAGCAAACCAAAGGAGUGUUUUUAUUCCUUAUCGUGAAUCUGUUCUUACAUGGCUGUUAAAAGAAAGUCUGGGUGGAAAUUCAAAAACUGCAAUGAUUGCUACGAUUAGUCCCGCUGCCAGCAACAUAGAAGAAACAUUAAGCACACUUAGAUAUGCUAACCAAGCCCGUUUAAUAGUCAACAUUGCUAAAGUAAAUGAAGAUAUGAACGCUAAGUUAAUUAGAGAAUUGAAGGCAGAAAUUGCAAAGCUAAAAGCUGCUCAGAGAAACAGUCGGAAUAUUGACCCUGAACGAUACAGGCUCUGUCGGCAAGAAAUAACAUCCUUAAGAAUGAAACUGCAUCAACAGGAGAGAGACAUGGCAGAAAUGCAAAGAGUGUGGAAAGAAAAGUUUGAACAAGCUGAAAAAAGAAAACUUCAAGAAACAAAAGAGUUACAGAAAGCAGGAAUUAUGUUUCAAAUGGACAAUCAUUUACCAAACCUUGUUAAUCUGAAUGAAGAUCCACAACUAUCUGAGAUGCUGCUAUAUAUGAUAAAAGAAGGAACAACUACAGUUGGAAAGUAUAAACCAAACUCAAGCCAUGAUAUUCAGUUAUCUGGGGUGCUGAUUGCUGAUGAUCAUUGUACUAUCAAAAAUUUUGGUGGGACAGUGAGUAUUAUCCCAGUUGGGGAAGCAAAGACAUAUGUAAAUGGAAAACAUAUUUUGGAAAUCACAGUAUUACGUCAUGGUGAUCGAGUGAUUCUUGGUGGAGAUCAUUAUUUUAGAUUUAAUCAUCCAGUAGAAGUCCAGAAAGGAAAAAGGCCAUCUGGAAGAGAUACUCCUAUAAGUGAGGGUCCAAAAGACUUUGAAUUUGCAAAAAAUGAGUUGCUCAUGGCACAGAGAUCACAACUUGAAGCAGAAAUAAAAGAGGCUCAGUUGAAGGCAAAGGAAGAAAUGAUGCAAGGAAUCCAGAUUGCAAAAGAAAUGGCUCAGCAAGAGCUUUCUUCUCAAAAAGCUGCAUAUGAAAGCAAAAUAAAAGCACUGGAAGCAGAACUGAGAGAAGAGUCUCAAAGGAAAAAAAUGCAGGAAAUAAAUAACCAGAAGGCUAAUCACAAAAUUGAGGAAUUAGAAAAGGCAAAGCAGCAUCUUGAACAGGAAAUAUAUGUCAACAAAAAGCGAUUAGAAAUGGAAACAUUGGCUACAAAACAGGCUUUAGAAGACCAUAGCAUCCGCCAUGCAAGAAUUCUGGAAGCUUUAGAAACUGAAAAGCAAAAAAUUGCUAAAGAAGUACAAAUUCUACAGCAGAAUCGGAAUAAUAGGGAUAAAACUUUUACAGUGCAGACAACUUGGAGCUCUAUGAAACUCUCAAUGAUGAUUCAGGAAGCCAAUGCUAUCAGCAGCAAAUUGAAAACAUACUAUGUUUUUGGCAGACAUGAUAUAUCAGAUAAAAGUAGUUCUGACACUUCUAUUCGGGUUCGUAACCUGAAACUAGGAAUCUCAACAUUCUGGAGUCUGGAAAAGUUUGAAUCUAAACUUGCAGCAAUGAAAGAACUUUAUGAGAGUAAUGGUAGUAACAGGGGUGAAGAUGCCUUUUGUGAUCCUGAAGAUGAAUGGGAACCCGACAUUACAGAUGCACCAGUUUCUUCACUUUCUAGAAGGAGGAGUAGGAGUUUGAUGAAGAACAGAAGAAUUUCUGGUUGUUUACAUGACAUACAAGUCCAUCCAAUUAAGAAUUUGCAUUCUUCACAUUCAUCAGGUUUAAUGGACAAAUCAAGCACUAUUUACUCAAAUUCAGCAGAGUCCUUUCUUCCUGGAAUUUGCAAAGAAUUGAUUGGUUCUUCGUUAGAUUUUUUUGGACAGAGUUAUGAUGAAGAAAGAACUAUAGCAGACAGCCUAAUUAAUAGUUUUCUUAAAAUUUAUAAUGGGCUAUUUGCCAUUUCCAAGGCUCAUGAAGAACAAGAUGAAGAAAGUCAAGAUAACUUGUUUUCUUCUGAUCGAGCAAUCCAGUCACUUACUAUUCAGACUGCAUGUGCUUUUGAGCAGCUAGUAGUGCUAAUGAAACACUGGCUGAGUGAUUUACUGCCUUGUACCAACAUAGCAAGACUUGAGGAUGAGUUGAGACAAGAAGUUAAAAAACUGGGAGGCUACUUACAGUUAUUUUUGCAGGGAUGCUGUUUGGAUAUUUCAUCAAUGAUAAAAGAGGCUCAAAAGAAUGCAAUCCAAAUUGUACAACAAGCUGUAAAGUAUGUGGGGCAGUUAGCAGUUCUGAAAGGGAGCAAGCUACAUUUUCUAGAAAACGGUAACAAUAAAGCUGCCAGUGUCCAGGAGGAAUUCAUGGAUGCUGUUUGUGAUGGUGUAGGCUUAGGAAUGAAGAUUUUAUUAGAUUCUGGACUGGAAAAAGCAAAAGAACUUCAGCAUGAACUCUUUAGGCAGUGUACAAAAAAUGAGGUUACCAAAGAAAUGAAAACUAAUGCCAUGGGAUUGAUUAGAUCUCUUGAAAACAUCUUUGCUGAAUCGAAAAUUAAAAGUUUCAGAAGGCAAGUACAAGAAGAAAACUUUGAAUACCAAGAUUUCAAGAGGAUGGUUAAUCGUGCUCCAGAAUUCUUAAAGUUAAAACAUUGCUUAGAGAAAGCUAUUGAAAUUAUUAUUUCUGCACUGAAAGGAUGCCAUAGUGAUAUAAAUCUUCUCCAGACUUGUGUUGAAAGUAUUCGCAACUUGGCCAGUGAUUUUUACAGUGACUUCAGUGUGCCUUCUACUUCUGUUGGCAGCUAUGAGAGUAGAGUAACUCACAUUGUCCACCAGGAACUAGAAUCUCUAGCUAAGUCUCUCCUCUUUUGUUUUGAAUCUGAAGAAAGCCCUGAUUUGUUGAAACCCUGGGAAACUUAUAAUCAAAAUACCAAAGAAGAACACCAACAAUCUAAAUCAAGCGGGAUUGACGGCAGUAAGAAUAAAGGUGUACCAAAGCGUGUCUAUGAGCUCCAUGGCUCAUCCCCAGCAGUGAGCUCAGAGGAAUGCACACCCAGUAGGAUUCAGUGGGUGUGAAUACUGAUGUGUAGGCACUUUUAUGACCACCCAUGAAAGAAAAAGAACACUUGCUCGGUAAUUUUCUUUAUGCAGGAGAGUUUAAGAGAAAUCAGCACAGAUAUUUCAAAAAAGUCCAUGUCUUUUUAUCUUUAAAAUAUCUAUUUAUCAAAGGCCAGACACAGUGGCUCACGCCUGUAAUCCCAGCACUUUGGGAGGCGGGCAGAUCACAAGGUCAGGAGUUUGAGACCGGCCUGGCCAACAUGGCGAAACCCCGUCUCUACUAAAAAUACAAAAAUUUGCUGGGCAUGGUGGCGCGUGCCUGUAAUCCCAGCUACUAGGGGGGCUGAGGCAGGAGGAUCGCUUGAACCUGAGAGGCAGAGGUUGCAGUGAGCCAAGAUCAUGCCACUUUACUCCAGUCUGAGCAACAGAACGAGACUUAGUCAAAAUAAAUAAAUAAAUAAAUAAAUAAAUAAAUAAAUAAAUAAAUAAAAUAUAUUUUUAUCUUUAAAGUGUUUAACAUUGGUAUACUGUCUGUAGUUGGUUCAUUAGUCGUUUAUAAAGGGUUAUUUUCUCAUGAGUGGAAACCUGAACAAUCAGUUACCUUUGUGCCUAUGCCUUCUCUCUCCUCAGACAGCUGGGAUGUUUAUGGUGAAAUGGCCUGUACAAGUUUAACUAAGACAACUUAACUUGCAUUGUUAAUCAAAAAUUCUUUUCUCAAAGGGUUAACUGGUUGCCAUUUUGAAUAGUAUGUUCAAGGGUGUAGCUUCCUGUUUCUUUCCAAAUUAUAAGUAGCUACCUAAAUAUAGUAUAAUUAUAUAUUAAUAAUAUGGCUUGCUGGCACAGUAGUUUACCCUGUUAUCUGUGUUUCAUAAUGGGGGCUGUAUGAAUAUUAUUUAAAACUAAUAAAAUGUUGCCAGAAUUAUACUAAACUGUUGGAUGAGAUUAGGAGAUCAGAGGCUGGACCUUCUCUUGAUAAUGCUUGUUUUGUUAAAGGUAUAAUGAAAUAAUUUGUAUAUGAUUUGAUGAAGAUUAAAGACCCUUAUUUUCCACAGCUUUAAAAAAAAACCUUUAUUUAUGAUCAAGUAAUAAAGAUAAUAUUCUACUUGUGGGAUCUUACAUUACGGAAAUAGUUUGACGUUUUUGACCUCAAGAGUAUGUAUAAUUUGAAGAGAUACUUUGUAACUAUGCUUGGGUGAUAUUGAGCAGUUCCUAAAGAAUAAUUCAUUUAAAAAAAAAGAAGAAAAAAAAAGAAGAAUUCAUUUAAAUAACCUGAUCCUUUCAUUUGCCCUUUUCGAAUUUACAGAUACUACUUGUACAUUUGGCAUAACUAGUUGAAAUUGGCCAUUCGUACCAUGAAUAAAUCUGAUAGUUUCCUUGUUAGGAAGAGAUUGUAAGUAAAUACAGUCAUUGCAGUCAGAACAGUAUUAGUGAACCUUGUGUGGUGUUUUCAAGCUCUUUAAAAUGGUACAAUGUAGCACAUUUGCUUUCAUUUCUUUUUUUAUUUUUGGCAUUUGACCUUGUAUUCUUUCUGAAGCUCUAUAUGUGUUUUUAUUAGUCAAUAAUCUGGCAAGUAGCACUUUGCCUGUGCAGUUUGCUGGAGUGUAGAUGUACAUAUGAGGAUUUCCCGGGAGGUGCACUUCUUUGAAGAACUUCCUAAAGUACCUGUAUAGUAGUUUUCAUCUUAAUAUUCAGUAUUUAAUCUUCAGUUUGUGCUUUGUAAACUCAUGACUUAAUUGGUCAGAAACUUUUUAGUGUCUUUAUAAAAUUUUGUAUACAUAUUUAUACUAAACACAUUGUGAUACUGUAUUUGAAUGAAUGGUGAAAAAAUAUUUGCUAUUGGAAUUAUGUGCACUGACAAGAAAUGUUAUAAAGAGAAUGCCUUUAAUAAAUCUUUUCAGCAUUAGAAUUG